AGUCUGCCCCGGCGGUCUCCGUUUGUUUGAACAGGAAGGCGGACAUAUUAGUCCCUCUCAGCCCCCCUCGCCCCACCCCCCAGGCAUUCGCCGCCGCGACUCGCCCUUUCCCCGGCUGGGACCGCAGCCCCUCCCAGAAGCUCCCCCAUCAGCAGCCGCCGGGACCCAACUAUCGUCUUCCUCUUCGCCCGCUCUCCAGCCUUUCCUCUGCUAAGUCUCCAUCGGGCAUCGACCUCGCCCUGCCCCACCGGACACCGUAGCAGCAGCCCCAGCAGCGACGGGACAAAAUGGGAGAGUGAGGCUGUCCUGCGUGGACCAGCUCGUGGCCGAGACUGAUCGGUGCGUCGGGCCGGGCCGAGUAGAGCCGGGGACGCGGGGCUAGACCGUCUACAGCGCCUCUGAGCGGAGCGGGCCCGGCCCGUGGCCCGAGCGGCGGCCGCAGCUGGCACAGCUCCUCACCCGCCCUUUGCUUUCGCCUUUCCUCUUCUCCCUCCCUUGUUGCCCGGAGGGAGUCUCCACCCUGCUUCUCUUUCUCUACCCGCUCCUGCCCAUCUCGGGACGGGGACCCCUCCAUGGCGACGGCGGCCGGGGCCCGCUAGACUGAAGCACCUCGCCGGAGCGACGAGGCUGGUGGCGACGGCGCUGUCGGCUGUCGUGAGGGGCUGCCGGGUGGGAUGCGACUUUGGGCGUCCGAGCGGCUGUGGGUCGCUGUUGCCCCCGGCCCGGGGUCUGGAGAGCGGAGGUCCCCUCAGUGAGGGGAAGACGGGGGAACCGGGCGCACCUGGUGACCCUGAGGUUCCGGCUCCUCCGCCCCGCGGCUGCGAACCCACCGCGGAGGAAGUUGGUUGAAAUUGCUUUCCGCUGCUGGUGCUGGUAAGAGGGCAUUGUCACAGCAGCAGCAACAUGUCGACUGGGGACAGUUUUGAGACUCGAUUUGAAAAAAUGGACAACCUGCUGCGGGAUCCCAAAUCGGAAGUGAAUUCGGAUUGUUUGCUGGAUGGAUUGGAUGCUUUGGUAUAUGAUUUGGAUUUUCCUGCCUUAAGAAAAAACAAAAAUAUUGACAACUUUUUAAGCAGAUAUAAAGACACAAUAAAUAAAAUCAGAGAUUUACGAAUGAAAGCUGAAGAUUAUGAAGUAGUGAAGGUGAUUGGUAGAGGUGCAUUUGGAGAAGUUCAAUUGGUAAGGCAUAAAUCCACCAGGAAGGUAUAUGCUAUGAAGCUUCUCAGCAAAUUUGAAAUGAUAAAGAGAUCUGAUUCUGCUUUUUUCUGGGAAGAAAGGGACAUCAUGGCUUUUGCCAACAGUCCUUGGGUUGUUCAGCUUUUUUAUGCAUUCCAAGAUGAUCGUUAUCUCUACAUGGUGAUGGAAUACAUGCCUGGUGGAGAUCUUGUAAACUUAAUGAGCAACUAUGAUGUGCCUGAAAAAUGGGCACGAUUCUAUACUGCAGAAGUAGUUCUUGCAUUGGAUGCAAUCCAUUCCAUGGGUUUUAUUCACAGAGAUGUGAAGCCUGAUAACAUGCUGCUGGAUAAAUCUGGACAUUUGAAGUUAGCAGAUUUUGGUACUUGUAUGAAGAUGAAUAAGGAAGGCAUGGUACGAUGUGAUACAGCGGUUGGAACACCUGAUUAUAUUUCCCCUGAAGUAUUAAAAUCCCAAGGUGGUGAUGGUUAUUAUGGAAGAGAAUGUGACUGGUGGUCGGUUGGGGUAUUUUUAUACGAAAUGCUUGUAGGUGAUACACCUUUUUAUGCAGAUUCUUUGGUUGGAACUUACAGUAAAAUUAUGAACCAUAAAAAUUCACUUACCUUUCCUGAUGAUAAUGACAUAUCAAAAGAAGCAAAAAACCUUAUUUGUGCCUUCCUUACUGACAGGGAAGUGAGGUUAGGGCGAAAUGGUGUAGAAGAAAUCAAACGACAUCUCUUCUUCAAAAAUGACCAGUGGGCUUGGGAAACGCUCCGAGACACUGUAGCACCAGUUGUACCCGAUUUAAGUAGUGACAUUGAUACUAGUAAUUUUGAUGACUUGGAAGAAGAUAAAGGAGAGGAAGAAACAUUCCCUAUUCCUAAAGCUUUCGUUGGCAAUCAACUACCUUUUGUAGGAUUUACAUAUUAUAGCAAUCGUAGAUACUUAUCUUCAGCAAAUCCUAAUGAUAACAGAACUAGCUCCAAUGCAGAUAAAAGCUUGCAGGAAAGUUUGCAAAAAACAAUCUAUAAGCUGGAAGAACAGCUGCAUAAUGAAAUGCAGUUAAAAGAUGAAAUGGAGCAGAAGUGCAGAACCUCAAACAUAAAACUAGACAAGAUAAUGAAAGAAUUGGAUGAAGAGGGAAAUCAAAGAAGAAAUCUAGAAUCUACAGUGUCUCAGAUUGAGAAGGAGAAAAUGUUGCUACAGCAUAGAAUUAAUGAGUACCAAAGAAAAGCUGAACAGGAAAAUGAGAAGAGAAGAAAUGUAGAAAAUGAAGUUUCUACAUUAAAGGAUCAGUUGGAAGACUUAAAGAAAGUCAGUCAGAAUUCACAGCUUGCUAAUGAGAAGCUGUCCCAGUUACAAAAGCAGCUAGAAGAAGCCAAUGACUUACUUAGGACAGAAUCGGACACAGCUGUAAGAUUGAGGAAGAGUCACACAGAGAUGAGCAAGUCAAUUAGUCAGUUAGAGUCCCUGAACAGAGAGUUGCAAGAGAGAAAUCGAAUUUUAGAGAAUUCUAAGUCACAAACAGACAAAGAUUAUUACCAGCUGCAAGCUAUAUUAGAAGCUGAACGAAGAGACAGAGGUCAUGAUUCUGAGAUGAUUGGAGACCUUCAAGCUCGAAUUACAUCUUUACAAGAGGAGGUGAAGCAUCUCAAACAUAAUCUCGAAAAAGUGGAAGGAGAAAGAAAAGAGGCUCAAGACAUGCUUAAUCACUCAGAAAAGGAAAAGAAUAAUUUAGAGAUAGAUUUAAACUACAAACUUAAAUCAUUACAACAACGGUUAGAACAAGAGGUAAAUGAACACAAAGUAACCAAAGCUCGUUUAACUGACAAACAUCAAUCUAUUGAAGAGGCAAAGUCUGUGGCAAUGUGUGAGAUGGAAAAAAAGCUGAAAGAAGAAAGAGAAGCUCGAGAGAAGGCUGAAAAUCGGGUUGUUCAGAUUGAGAAACAGUGUUCCAUGCUAGACGUUGAUCUGAAGCAAUCUCAGCAGAAACUAGAACAUUUGACUGGAAAUAAAGAAAGGAUGGAGGAUGAAGUUAAGAAUCUAACCCUGCAACUGGAGCAGGAAUCAAAUAAGCGGCUGUUGUUACAAAAUGAAUUGAAGACUCAAGCAUUUGAGGCAGACAAUUUAAAAGGUUUAGAAAAGCAGAUGAAACAGGAAAUAAAUACUUUAUUGGAAGCAAAGAGAUUAUUAGAAUUUGAGUUAGCUCAGCUUACGAAACAGUAUAGAGGAAAUGAAGGACAGAUGCGGGAGCUACAAGAUCAGCUUGAAGCUGAGCAAUAUUUCUCGACACUUUAUAAAACCCAGGUAAAGGAACUUAAAGAAGAAAUUGAAGAAAAAAACAGAGAAAAUUUAAAGAAAAUACAGGAACUACAAAAUGAAAAAGAAACUCUUGCUACUCAGUUGGAUCUAGCAGAAACAAAAGCUGAGUCUGAGCAGUUGGCGCGAGGCCUUCUGGAAGAACAGUAUUUUGAAUUGACGCAAGAAAGCAAGAAAGCUGCUUCAAGAAAUAGACAAGAGAUUACAGAUAAAGAUCACACUGUUAGUCGGCUUGAAGAAGCAAACAGCAUGCUAACCAAAGAUAUUGAAAUAUUAAGAAGAGAGAAUGAAGAGCUAACAGAGAAAAUGAAGAAGGCAGAGGAAGAAUAUAAACUGGAGAAGGAGGAGGAGAUCAGUAAUCUUAAGGCUGCCUUUGAAAAGAAUAUCAACACUGAACGAACCCUUAAAACACAGGCUGUUAACAAAUUGGCAGAAAUAAUGAAUCGAAAAGAUUUUAAAAUUGAUAGAAAGAAAGCUAAUACACAAGAUUUGAGAAAGAAAGAAAAGGAAAAUCGAAAGCUGCAACUGGAACUCAACCAAGAAAGAGAGAAAUUCAACCAGAUGGUAGUGAAACAUCAGAAGGAACUGAAUGACAUGCAAGCGCAAUUGGUAGAAGAAUGUGCACAUAGGAAUGAGCUUCAGAUGCAGUUGGCCAGCAAAGAGAGUGAUAUUGAGCAAUUGCGUGCUAAACUUUUGGACCUCUCGGAUUCUACAAGUGUUGCUAGUUUUCCUAGUGCUGAUGAAACUGAUGGUAACCUCCCAGAGUCAAGAAUUGAAGGUUGGCUUUCAGUACCAAAUAGAGGAAAUAUCAAACGAUAUGGCUGGAAGAAACAGUAUGUUGUGGUAAGCAGCAAAAAAAUUUUGUUCUAUAAUGACGAACAAGAUAAGGAGCAAUCCAAUCCAUCUAUGGUAUUGGACAUAGAUAAACUGUUUCACGUUAGACCUGUAACCCAAGGAGAUGUGUAUAGAGCUGAAACUGAAGAAAUUCCUAAAAUAUUCCAGAUACUAUAUGCAAAUGAAGGUGAAUGUAGAAAAGAUGUAGAGAUGGAACCAGUACAACAAGCUGAAAAAACUAAUUUCCAAAAUCACAAAGGCCAUGAGUUUAUUCCUACACUCUACCACUUUCCUGCCAAUUGUGAUGCCUGUGCCAAACCUCUCUGGCAUGUUUUUAAGCCACCCCCUGCCCUAGAGUGUCGAAGAUGCCAUGUUAAGUGCCACAGAGAUCACUUAGAUAAGAAAGAGGACUUAAUUUGUCCAUGUAAAGUAAGUUAUGAUGUAACAUCAGCAAGAGAUAUGCUGCUGUUAGCAUGUUCUCAGGAUGAACAAAAAAAAUGGGUAACUCAUUUAGUAAAGAAAAUCCCUAAGAAUCCACCAUCUGGUUUUGUUCGUGCUUCCCCUCGAACGCUUUCUACAAGAUCCACUGCAAAUCAGUCUUUCCGGAAAGUGGUCAAAAAUACAUCUGGAAAAACUAGUUAACCAUGUGACUGAGUGCCCUGUGGAAUCGUGUGGGAUGCUACCUGAUAAACCAGGCUUCUUUAACCAUGCAGAGCAGACAGGCUGUUUCUUUGACACAAAUAUCACAGGCUUCAGGGUUAAGAUUGCUGUUUUUCUGUCCUUGCUUUGGCACAACACACUGAGGGUUUUUUUUAUUGCGGGUUUGCCUACAGGUAGAUUAGAUUAAUUAUUACUAUGUAAUGCAAGUACAGUUGGGGGAAAGCUUAGGUAGAUAUAUUUUUUUUAAAAGGUGCUGCCUUUUUGGAUUUAUAAGAAAAUGCCUGUCAGUCGUGAUAGAACAGAGUUUUCCUCAUAUGAGUAAGAGGAAGGGACUUUCACUUUCAAGUGGAACAGCCAUCACUAUCAAGAUCAGCUCAUGGAAGGAGUAAAGAAAAUAUCUCAAAAUGAGACAAACUGAAGUUUUGUUUUUUUUUUAAUGACUUAAGUUUUUGUGCUCUUGCAAGACUAUACAAAACUAUUUUAAGAAAGCAGUGAUAUCACUUGAACUUCAGUGCCCUCACUGUAGAAUUUAAAAGCCUUACUGUUGAUUGCCCAUGUUGGACUUGAUGGAGAAAUUAAAUAUCUUUCAUUAUGCUUUACAAAAUACUGUAUAUGUUUCAGCAAGUUUGGGGAAUGGGAGAGGACAAAAAAAAGUUACAUUUAAUCUAUGCAUUUUUGCCAAGCCAUAUUGAGUUAUUUUACUACUAGAGACAUUAGGAAACUAACUGUACAAAAGAACCAAGUUUAAAAGCAUUUUGUGGGGUACAUCAUUUCUAUAAUUGUAUAAUGUAUUUCUUUGUGGUUUUAAAUGAUAAAGACAUUAAGUUAACAAACAUAUAAGAAAUGUAUGCACUGUUUGAAAUGUAAAUUAUUCUUAGAACACUUUCAAUGGGGGUUGCAUUGUCCUUUUAGUGCCUUAAUUUGAGAUAAUUAUUUUACUGCCAUGAGUAAGUAUAGAAAUUUCAAAAAAUGUAUUUUCAAAAAAUUAUGUGUGUCAGUGAGUUUUUCAUUGAUAAUUGGUUUAAUUUAAAAUAUUUAGAGGUUUGUUGGACUUUCAUAAAUUGAGUACAAUCUUUGCAUCAAACUACCUGCUACAAUAAUGACUUUAUAAAACUGCAAAAAAUGUAGAAGGUUGCACCAACAUAAAAAGGAAAUAUGGCAAUACAUCCAUGAUGUUUUCCAGUUAACAUAGGAAUUACCAGAUAAAUACUGUUAAACUCUUGUCCAGUAACAAGAGUUGAUUCAUAUGGACAGUAUGAUUUAUUGUUUAUUUUUUUAACCAAAUACCUCCUCAGUAAUUUAUAAUGGCUUUGCAGUAAUGUGUAUCAGAUAAGAAGCACUGGAAAACCGAUCGUCUCUAGGAUGAUAUGCAUGUUUCAAGUGGUAUUGAAAGCCGCACUGAUGGAUAUGUAAUAAUAAACAUAUCUGUUAUUAAUAUACUAAUGACUCUGUGCUCAUUUAAUGAGAAAUAAAAGUAAUUUAUGGAUGGGUAUCUUUAAUUUUUACUGCAAUGUGUUUUCUCAUGGCUGAAAUGAAUGGAAAACAUACUUCAAAUUAGUCUCUGAUUGUAUAUAAAUGUUUGUGAAAUUCCAUGGUUAGAUUAAAGUGUAUUUUUAAAAGAUAAAACGUGGUCUUGGGCUCUAAAACAAGAGUGGGAAUAGUUCACAUGAAAAGCUGGCUAAAGUGUGUUGGAAAACAAUUCUCCAUGGGUCUCUUGCAUUUCUACACAUCAGGGAAGCAGAGGCUCUGACAACCUUUCUUUUGACUAUCUUUUCCAAGGAUAUUUAUGUAGUAAACAGCCUUGGAAGAUAGAGUUCUCCCUUGUGAGGAUGUCGGGUUCUUUUACUGUCCAGUAUAAUAAAGAUAACGUCUCCCACCUAUGAUGCAAACCCACUGUGUGCUCAGCACCCACCUGGGCCACUCUGCAUUGCCCACAUGGGGCUUGGAGGGCAAAGGGAACUGAUGGAACGUGAAACUUAUGCUGCUUUUGCUGUGCUGUGAAUGAAGUCAUCUGACUCUGACCCAGGGGUCUCAUCUCUUUUGUCAGGAUCCAUGAAACUGUGACUGGCAGCAUGCAAACAGGAUAAAAUCUCAGCACAGUUCCUGACGGUGUCCUUACUACCUUCUCAGACUCAUCACCAUUACCUAAUAUUUUAAGGUCCAGUUGCAGAGAACAGAGUUAAUUCUAAUUAGUUUAAGCAAGAGAAGACUUUCCAAAUGACAUACUAAUCUGAACUUAGAAUUGUUGAGAACUGAGAGAGCUUUGAGGAAUCACUCCCAAUGCCACAUUACAGAACUGGGUCAACCAGGAGAGCUGCUUCCUCUUCUAAGUUCAGGAAACCACUCACUCCCAAGUAUACCAAUAUUGAGAGGGUCCAGAUAGUGCCAUAAUCAGGAAUCCACACUACCACUGCUGGUUCUCUGCAACACUUGUCAGGCUUGCUACAAUCUACCUCCAGUUAGAUGUUUUGUACCAUUCCUCUUGCCACUUAAGAACCUCAUGUCUGCACACUGCCUCAGAAAAGGCACUUCCAUGACCCUGCUUGCUGGCAUUUAGCACAGCCUGCAUCUCACGUCUGCCUUCUCUAGGUGCAUCUACGUGGCCAAAAUUAAAUCACAUCCAGACCCCUAGCUGCAAGAAAGUCUGAGAAAUAUAGCCUCUAGCUUUCUCUCUAAUUUGUUACAGGAGGACACACUAGGAGUGUGGAAUGAAGGUUCAGCAUUGAGUUAGCCCAUGCACCCACACCUGUAAGCUUCUCUGAGAUCAGGAACUCCAGCUUUGGGCAACAAAGAAAACAUAGCCACUGUCAUUAUUCACAGGUUCACUCAUGACCUGUCAUUUGGGGUUUCAGCUUAAAUUAACCCAUUCACCCUUCAUUUAAAGUAAAAAAAAUAAGUAAAAGAACUUAAAUGACAAACUCAUAGUUACUUGAGUUUGUAAUUCAUAGUUAACUUUCACAGUUCUAUAAUCAAUCUGGAAUUCAGAGUGAGGUAGAGAUCAAGCAGUAUUUCUCCCAUAUGGAUAUUCAGUUGAUACUGCAGUAUUCAUUGAAAAUACUUCUUUCCUGCAUCGUAAUUCAGGUGAACAAUCCAUUGGUGUUAUUUCUGUGUCCUUGCCAAUAUCACACUUUUAAUUACUGUAACUUUAUAAUAAGAUUUUAUAUCUGUAGUAGAAGUCCAACUUUGUAAUCCCUCCCAAUUGGCUUGGCUAUUCUUGGCCUUUUGCAUUUCCAUAUAAUUUUUUAUUUUUGUUUUGAAACGAAGUUUCGCUCUUGUUGCCCAGGCUGGAGUGCAGUGGCGCGAUCUCGGCUCACUGCAACCUCCGCCUCCCAGGUUCAAGUGAUCCUCCUGCCUCAGACUCCCGAGUAGCUGGGAUUACAGGUGCCCACCACCAUGCCCAGCUAAUUUUUGUAUUUUUAGUAGAGACAGGGUUUCACCAUGUUGGCCAGCCUGGUCUUGAACUCCUGACCUCAGGUGAUCCACACCCACCUUGGCCUCCCAAAGUGCUGGGAUUACAGGCAUGAGCCACCGCGCCUGGUUGCAUUCCCAUAUAAAUUUAAAAACAAUCUACUGAAAGAUGUAUACGACCUCCACCAAGAAAAUUGUAAGACAUUUGGAGAAGUUUAAAAAGACAUGAAUAAACGGAAAUGGUUUUUUUAAAUAAACAAAUGAUUUUUAAAGUUGAUCAUUAGGUUAAUAAAUAGUCAUAUAAUGACAAUCCGAUGAGAUUAUGUUGCCCAGGGUGGUCUCUAACUCCUAGCCUCAAGCAGUUUUACUCUCUCAUUACAGGUGUAGGCCACCGUGCCUGGCCUGACACUUGGAAAUCUUAAUCACAAUUAUUCUUUGUUUUUAUAAUGUUUACUGUUCAAAUCAAUUUCUGGUUGGAUAGUAUGUAUAUAUAAAGCCAUGCUCAAUGGCCUAGAUAUAUUUACUGCCAAAUCUUUUAUGCUUUUAGUGUUUUUUUUCUGGACAAGAUCUAUGCUUAUUGCAAUAAAUUAAAUGCAAAGAAUAUUCUAGUAGAAAGUCAGUCUGCACUUCCUAAACCCCACCCCACCCCACCAAUUCCUUCAUAACUGUUAUUAACAGUUAGCUGUGUUUUCUAAUGGAUUAUCUCCAAAGUAUAUGUAACUCAGAUUUUUGUGAGGUAGGAAAAGAAUAACAUUAAUUCCACUUCACAUAUUGAAAGUCUAACAUACAAAGAGAUUAAAUAUCUCCUUUCUUUUGCCAAAUGUUAAUGAAUUGUCUUAUGAGAAUUAAGAUAUGAUACUUUCUCCCAAGCUAUACUGUUUCCCAUAAAGUAUUUGAGAUGUUGGAGAUUCAAGGGAAAAAAUAUAAAUGCUUAGAAAUAAAGUGUAUAAUGCAAAGAUUGUGAAUAAAGUGACACUUGUAUGUUAAUCCUAUAAAUUGGUUUCUUGUACCAUGUAGGAUGGUUUGGCUAUUAAAUUGAAUUAAGUGGUUCA